ACGGUGGCGUUUCAGAGGACUCCGGUCCUGGAGAGGCACCCCUGGGUUGCAGAGAACACAGACGUCUCGAAGGGACAGAGAAGGACGCACCAUUGUAAGCCCCUCUUAGUAAACCCUCUGAGAAGUAGAGGCCGGGGCGAGUUCCCAGGUGUCGUCCUGAGCAAACUGCCCUCUUUUGUCAGCCCUGAGCUUUCCUGGGCUGGACCUCAGAGGGGGCUGGGUGGUCCCAGGGCGCGACCUUGGGCUGCCAGAAGCCACGCUAGGGUUGGUCAAGGCUCUCAGUGCAAGGUUUCGACAUAGUCGUUCUGUGCUGCGUUCUGCAGUUGUCAGCUGUCACCUGCAAACCUCAGCAGCUCCCCUUAGGGCGUGGUGGGCAAACAGUGUCAGUGAUGCGUGUCCACAGCCUCGGGAAACACUUCAGGUCCACGUUUUCGUAUGUUGUCACUAGAUCUCGGCCCUUCCGACCGAAAGGCUUCGGCACCUCACGCGGUGGGUCCCAUGCUUGUCCUGUUAAAUACUCUUGAACUCUAUUCUGUCCUGAUACUGAAUAAUGCAAGAAUGGGUGGUUCCAGUUUUCAUCCCUAUAAACCGUACAUCUUUGUGCCAGCUGUUCAUCCCUGACUGUUGAGAGAGGACCCUGCUGCAGCCUCCCUGUGGCCAGUAGCACAGUUCUCAUCCCUUCCCAGUCCUCUCUCCGGCCAUGUCAACAGUGAGAGGUGGGUCGUUUCCAUCCCCUUUGGGGGGCUGCGGAUUCACCCCUGUGGGAAAUGGCACCUCAUCAUGGUAGGGGCUCUUGUUCCCUUUCAGCUCCCGAUUCUCCUGAAGGGGACGUCCGAUGAUGAUGUCCCGUGUCCGGGCUACCUGUUUGAAGAGAUUGCUACCGCAGAAAUCUCCCACGAGUCUCCGGGCAGCAGCCAGUGCCUGCUGGAGUACCUCCUGAGCCGCCUGCACAGCAGCUCCGGCCACGGGAAGCUCAAGGUGCUGAAGAUCCUGCUCUAUCUGUGCAGCCACGGCUCCUCCUUCUUCCUGCUCAUCCUCAAACGCAACUCUGCCUUCAUCCAGGAAGCUGCAGCUUUUGCAGGGCCCCCAGAUCCUCUGCACGGGAACAGCUUGUACCAGAAGGUUCGCGCGGCCGCGCAGGACUUGGGGAGCACCCUGUUCUCGGACACCGUGUUGCCGCUGGCUCCCUCCCAGCCUCUGGGGACCCCGCCUGCCACAGGCAUGGGCUCCCAGGCCAGGCCGCACAGCACCCUCCAGGGUUUCGGCUACAGCAAGGAACACGGCCGCACGGGCUCGGCAGGCGAAGCCUUCCUCUCCACCAUCCAGAAGGCCGCAGAGGUGGUGGCCAGCGCCAUGCGCCCCGGGCCCGAGAGUCCCAGUACCCGGAGGCUCCUGCCGCGGGGUGACACCUACCAGCCUGCCAUGAUGCCUUCAGCCAGCCACGGUCCCCCAACCCUGGGGAACCUACUCCCCGGGGCCAUUCCAGGUCCCCGAGCUGUGAGGCAUCAGCCUGGGCAGGCCGGAGGGGGCUGGGAUGAGCUGGACAGCGGCCCCAGCUCUCAGAAUUCCUCCCAGAACAGCGACCUGAGCAGGGUCUCGGACUCGGGCAGUCAUUCCGGCAGCGACAGCCAUUCAGGGGCCAGCCGGGAGCCGGGUGACCUGGCAGAAAGGGUCGAGGUGGUGGCCCUGAGUGACUGUCAGCAGGAGUUGAGCUUGGUGAGGACUGUGACUCGGGGACCACGCGCCUUCCUGAGCCGCGAGGAGGCACAGCACUUCAUCAAAGCGUGUGGACUGCUCAACUGUGAGGCCGUGCUGCAGCUGCUGACCUGCCACCUGCGUGGGACCAGUGAAUGCACGCAGCUGAGGGCGCUGUGUGCCAUCGCCUCCCUGGGGAGCAGCGACCUCCUCCCCCAGGAGCACAUCCUCCUCCGCACCCGGCCGUGGCUGCAGGAGCUCAGCAUGGGCAGCCCGGGACCUGUGACCAACAAGGCCACCAAGAUCCUGAGGCACUUUGAGGCCUCCUGUGGGCAGCUGUCCCCUGCCCGGGGCACCUCAGCUGAGCCUGGCCCCACAGCCGCCCUCCCAGGCCCAUCUGACCUGCUGACCGACGCUGUGCCUCUCCCUGGGAGCCAGGUCUUCCUGCAGCCUCUGAGUUCAACCCCGGUCUCGUCCCGGAGCCCUGCUCCCUCAUCUGGGAUGCCGUCCAGCCCUGUGCCCACCCCACCCCCAGAUGCCUCCCCCAUUCCAGCCCCCGGAGACCCCAGCGAGGCCGAGGCCAGACUGGCAGAAAGCAGGCGGUGGAGACCUGAACGGAUCCCAGGGGGCACGGACAGCCCAAAGAGAGGCCCCAGCAGCUGUGCGUGGAGCCGCGACUCCUUGUUUGCUGGCAUGGAGCUGGUGGCCUGUCCCCGCCUGGUGGGGGCUGGGGCUGCUGCGGGAGAGUCCUGUCCUGAUGCUCCCCGCGCCCCCCAAACAUCGUCCCAGAGGACAGCAGCCAAAGAGCCUCCUGGCUCAGAGCCGUCAGCUUUCGCGUUCCUGAACGCCUGACCCGAUGGCCUGGCCCUGGAGUCUUCAGCUUCAGCUGCUGUCUGGGGCGGUCUGUGCUUCCUGAGCAGCCUCAACCGUAGCUGCUACAGUCUCCAGGCAGCUUGACUUGAGAGGACGACCCUAGGGCUACCUCAGUUUCCCCCAUCUCCUCUGCCAGAGGCUCUGGCUAUUUGGACUUGAAUCCCUACGAGGGAUGGCAGGUGGCAGGGCUUCAGAAAUGUCGAUCUCAGGGCUCUCAGGGGGCAGUCCCUGCCUGUCUUGCUCUCAGACAUGAGGUUUCUUGUAUGAAUGCGGAAGCGACUACCAGGUUCCUUAUUUCAUUUUGAUCUCAGCUCCCUCCUUCCCCAGGAGGUCAUGAGCAGCAACAAGCCACUGCUCCCCCGUCCCAUCGGGGUGGGCUAGGUGCUGAGGCUGGGUUUGGUGCAUGUGGGUUGAGGGUGUCUUGUCCGGGCUGCCUUGUGCUGUCUGGCCUGAGGCCAUUUCAAGUCUCAGAUCCCUACGUGAUCCUUCCCUGGCUCUCACCUGCUCCUUUAGGCUGUAAUUGCUUCCUACACACGAAGCCUCUGAUUGGAGCCUCUGGUCCAUCUCAGAAAAACCUUCCAAGAGCGCUGGGGUUUAUGCUUUCUGAAUAAACACUACUGUUUACAUGAA